UCUCAUCUGCUCCUCUACCUGCUCCACCCUCAAUCCACCAGAACCAUGGGCUGCUGUGGCUGCUCUGGAGGCUGUGGCUCCGGCUGUGGGGGCUGUGGCUCCGGCUGUGGGGGCUGUGGCUCUGGCUGUGGGGGCUGUGGUUCCGGCUGUGGGGGCUGUGGCUCCGGCUGUGGGGGCUGUGGCUCCAGCUGCUGUGUGCCCAUCUGCUGCUGCAAACCUGUGUGCUGCUGUGUGCCAGCCUGUUCCUGCUCCAGCUGUGGCUCCUGUGGGGGCUCCAAGGGGGGCUAUGGCUCUUGUGGGGGUUCCAAGGGGGGCUGUGUCUCCUGUGGGGGUUCCAAGGGGGGCUGUGGCUCCUGUGGGGGCUCCAAGGGGGGCUGUGGCUCCUGUGGGGGUUCCAAGGGGGGCUGUGGCUCCUGUGGGGGCUCCAAGGGGGGCUGUGUCUCCUGUGGGGGUUCCAAGGGGGGCUGUGGCUCCUGUGGGGGUUCCAAGGGGGGCUGUGUCUCCUGUGGGGGGUCCAAGGGGGGCUGUGGCUCCUGUGGGGGCUCCAAGGGGGGCUGUGGCUCCUGUGGGGGUUCCAAGGGGGGCUGUGGCUCCUGUGGGGGCUCCAAAGGAGGCUGUGGCUCUUGUGGCUGCUCCCAGUGCAGCUGCUGUAAGCCCUGCUGCUGCUCUUCAGGCUGUGGGUCAUCCUGCUGCCAGUCCAGCUGCUGUAAGCCCUGCUGCUCCUCCUCAGGUUGUGGGUCAUCCUGCUGCCAGUCCAGCUGCUGCAAGCCCUACUGCUGCCAGUCCAGCUGCUGUAAGCCCUGCUGCUCCUCCUCAGGUUGUGGGUCAUCCUGCUGCCAGUCCAGUUGCUGCAAUCCCUGCUGCUCCCAGUCUAGUUGCUGUGUCCCUGUGUGCUGCCAGUGUAAGAUCUGAGGCUCUGGACUCAGGCCUCAUGUGAGUCCUGCUAAUCCUGUCUUCCAAAGCUGUGACCUGUCCUUCAUUGUUGAGCCCCAAAUCAUUGCUCAGGGUCCAUUCCCUGCUGUAGAACGAUGCCAUAUCUGGCUGCCUUUUCCUAAGAAGAGUCCACCCUAAUUAAUGUCCAUUGUCUCUCCUAACAAAUUCUCUCCCCAAGUCAACUGCAAUUGCAGCUGAAUCACCCCUCACCCACUAGCCUCGCCUUUGCUCAUCUUUUCAGAGGCCUGAGCUCCUGAACCCACUUGCAGUCCUGUCUUUUCCAGCUGGAGCAGCUGGGCAUAAGCGUCCCACCUGCUACAAGGUGGGCGUUUAAGAGGCUUCCUUGGAGUGGCUUUGCAUGUCCAACACUCUGCUGUAUCUUUUUUUUUUUUUUUUUUUUUGAGAUGGAGUCUCGCACUGUCACCC